GCUCUGCUCCAGGCAUCUGCCACAAUGUGGGUGCUUACACCUGCUGCUUUUGCUGGGAAGCUCUUGAGUGUGUUCAGGCAACCUCUGAGCUCUCUGUGGAGGAGCCUGGUCCCGCUGUUCUGCUGGCUGAGGGCAACCUUCUGGCUGCUAGCUACCAAGAGGAGAAAGCAGCAGCUGGUCCUGAGAGGGCCAGAUGAGACCAAAGAGGAGGAAGAGGACCCUCCUCUGCCCACCACCCCAACCAGCGUCAACUAUCACUUCACUCGCCAGUGCAACUACAAAUGCGGCUUCUGUUUCCACACAGCCAAAACAUCCUUUGUGCUGCCCCUUGAGGAAGCAAAGAGAGGAUUGCUUUUGCUUAAGGAAGCUGGUAUGGAGAAGAUCAACUUUUCAGGUGGAGAGCCAUUUCUUCAAGACCGGGGAGAAUACCUGGGCAAGUUGGUGAGGUUCUGCAAAGUAGAGUUGCGGCUGCCCAGCGUGAGCAUCGUGAGCAAUGGAAGCCUGAUCCGGGAGAGGUGGUUCCAGAAUUAUGGUGAGUAUUUGGACAUUCUCGCUAUCUCCUGUGACAGCUUUGACGAGGAAGUCAAUGUCCUUAUUGGCCGUGGCCAAGGAAAGAAGAACCAUGUGGAAAACCUUCAAAAGCUGAGGAGGUGGUGUAGGGAUUAUAGAGUCGCUUUCAAGAUAAAUUCUGUCAUUAAUCGUUUCAACGUGGAAGAGGACAUGACGGAACAGAUCAAAGCACUAAACCCUGUCCGCUGGAAAGUGUUCCAGUGCCUCUUAAUUGAGGGUGAGAAUUGUGGAGAAGAUGCUCUAAGAGAAGCAGAAAGAUUUGUUAUUGGUGAUGAAGAAUUUGAAAGAUUCUUGGAGCGCCACAAAGAAGUGUCCUGCUUGGUGCCUGAAUCUAACCAGAAGAUGAAAGACUCCUACCUUAUUCUGGAUGAAUAUAUGCGCUUUCUGAACUGUAGAAAGGGACGGAAGGACCCUUCCAAGUCCAUCCUGGAUGUUGGUGUAGAAGAAGCUAUAAAAUUCAGUGGAUUUGAUGAAAAGAUGUUUCUGAAGCGAGGAGGAAAAUACAUAUGGAGUAAGGCUGAUCUGAAGCUGGAUUGGUAGAGCGGAAAGUGGAACGAGACUUCAACACACCAGUGGGAAAACUCCUAGAGUAACUGCCAUUGUCUGCAAUACUAUCCCGUUGGUAUUUCCCAGUGGCUGAAAACCUGAUUUUCUGCUGCACGUGGCAUCUGAUUACCUGUGGUCACUGAACACACGAAUAACUUGGAUAGCAAAUCCUGAGACAAUGGAAAACCAUUAACUUUACUUCAUUGGCUUAUAACCUUGUUGUUAUUGAAACAGCACUUCUGUUUUUGAGUUUGUUUUAGCUAAAAAGAAGGAAUACACACAGGAAUAAUGACCCCAAAAAUGCUUAGAUAAGGCCCCUAUACACAGGACCUGACAUUUAGCUCAAUGAUGCGUUUGUAAGAAAUAAGCUCUAGUGAUAUCUGUGGGGGCAAAAUUUAAUUUGGAUUUGAUUUUUUAAAACAAUGUUUACUGCGAUUUCUAUAUUUCCAUUUUGAAACUAUUUCUUGUUCCAGGUUUGUUCAUUUGACAGAGUCAGUAUUUUUUGCCAAAUAUCCAGAUAACCAGUUUUCACAUCUGAGACAUUACAAAGUAUCUGCCUCAAUUAUUUCUGCUGGUUAUAAUGCUUUUUUUUUUUUGCCUUUAUGCCAUUGCAGUCUUGUACUUUUUACUGUGAUGUACAGAAAUAGUCAACAGAUGUUUCCAAGAACAUAUGAUAUGAUAAUCCUACCAAUUUUCAAGAAGUCUCUAGAAAGAGAUAACACAUGGAAAGACGGUGUGGUGCAGCCCAGCCCACGGUGGCUGUUCCAUGAAUGCUGGCUACCUAUGUGUGUGGUACCUGUUGUGUCCCUUUCUCUUCAAAGAUCCUGAGCAAAACAAAGAUACGCUUUCCAUUUGAUGAUGGAGUUGACAUGGAGGCAGUGCUUGCAUUGCUUUGUUCGCCUAUCAUCUGGCCACAUGAGGCUGUCAAGCAAAAGAAUAGGAGUGUAGUUGAGUAGCUGGUUGGCCCUACAUCUCUGAGAAGUGACGGCACACUGGGUUGGCAUAAGAUAUCCUAAAAUCACGCUGGAACCUUGGGCAAGGAAGAAUGUGAGCAAGAGUAGAGAGAGUGCCUGGAUUUCAUGUCAGUGAAGCCAAGUCACCAUAUCAUAUUUUUGAAUGAACUCUGAGUCAGUUGAAAUAGGGUACCAUCUAGGUCAGUUUAAGAAGAGUCAGCUCAGAGAAAGCAAGCAUAAGGGAAAAUGUCACGUAAACUAGAUCAGGGAACAAAAUCCUCUCCUUGUGGAAAUAUCCCAUGCAGUUUGUUGAUACAACUUAGUAUCUUAUUGCCUAAAAAAAAAUUUCUUAUCAUUGUUUCAAAAAAGCAAAAUCAUGGAAAAUUUUUGUUGUCCAGGCAAAUAAAAGGUCAUUUUAAUUUAGCUGCAAUUUCAGUGUUCCUCACUAGGUGGCAUUUAAAUGUCGCCUGAUGUCAUUAAGCACCAUCCAAAAAGUCUGCUUCAUAAUCUAUUUUCAAGACUUGGUGAUUCUGAAAGUUUUGGUUUUUGUGACUUUGUUUCUCAGGAAAAAAAAUAUUCCUACUUAAAUUUUAAGUCUAUAAUUCAAUUUAAAUAUGUGUGUGUCUCAUCCAGGAUAGGAUAGGUUGUCUUCUAUUUUCCAUUUUACCUAUUUACUUUUUUUGUAAGAAAAGAGAAAAAUGAAUUCUAAAGAUGUUCCCCAUGGGUUUUGAUUGUGUCUAAGCUAUGAUGACCUUCAUAUAAUCAGCAUAAACAUAAAACAAAUUUUUUACUUAACAUGAGUGCACUUUACUAAUCCUCAUGGCACAGUGGCUCACGCCUGUAAUCCCAGCACUUGGGAGGACAAUGUGGGUGGAUCACGAGGUCAGGAGUUCGAGAACAGCCUGGCCAACAUGGUGAAACCCCGUCUCCACUAAAAAUACAAAAAUUAGCCAGGCAUGGUGGCGUACACUUGUAAUUCCAGCUACUCAAGAGGCUGAGGCAGGAGGAUUGCUUGAACCCUGAAGGCAGAGGUUACAGAGCCAAGAUAGCGCCACUGCACUCCAGCCUGGAUGACAGAGCAAGACUCCGUCUCAAAAAAAAAAAAAAAAAAAAGCAAGAGAGUUCAACUAAGAAAGGUCACAUAUGUGAAAGCCCAAGGACACUGUUUGAUAUACAGCAGGUAUUCAAUCAGUGUUAUUUGAAACCAAAUCUGAAUUUGAAGUUUGAAUCUUCUGAGUUGGAAUGAAUUUUUUUCUAGCUGAGGGAAACUGUAUUUUUCUUUCCCCAAAGAGGAAUGUAAUGUAAAGUGAAAUAAAACUAUAAGCUAUGUUAAAUACA